CUUAGUCCUCAAACCUCUUCUGUUUACACCCCUUCCCAGGUGAUUCUGUGACUUUACCAUCUAUAUAUCUUGACUUCUAAAUUUUUGUCUCAGCCUAAAUCUCUGCCCUGAGCACCAGAGUUGGAAAUCUUACUGCCUUCAUCUCUACUCAACAUCUCCACUUGGCUGUCUAAUAGGUAUCUCAGACUUGAGAUAUCCAAAGCAAACCGAAUUCUCUCCCAGCCCCACACCACCACCAUCCUGUAGUCUUUACUGUGAAUUAAGGGCACCUCCAUUUACCCAGCUGCCCAGAGUCAUUUUGGACACAUCUGUUUCUCUCAUGUCCCACAUCCAAUCCAUCAUCAAAUACUGUUUUUAUCUGCAGAAUAUAUCCAGACUCUAAUCAUGCCUUCUCACCUCCACUGCCCCCACCCUGGUCUAAGACACCAUCAUCUCUUGCCUAUAGACUAUUGCAAUGGCCCCCUAACUGAUCUUCACGCAUGCAUCUUGUGUGGAGGGUUCUCCACGCAGCAGCCAGUCAGACUUUCACUCUCUGCUGAGACCUAACCAGUGGCUUUCCAUCUCAUUCUGUCCUUUCACUCCUUACAAGGGCCUACUCCAAGGCCCAUGUUUCCUCUGAUCAGACAUUCCAACCACUCACCCCUUCAGCCCCCCUAUUCCAACCCAGUGGCCUCCUUGCUUUUCUUCCAACACAUCAAGCAAAAUUCUAUCCCAGGAUAUUUGUACCUGCUAUUCUGACCGUAGUGCUCGUCCCUAGGUAUCCACGUAGUCAUAGCUCUCUUCCUCCCCUCCUUCAAUUCCUGCUCACUGAGUUCUUCAACACUUAUAUAAUAGUAUCUCUUGCAUGGUGAUUUGAAAUACCUUCACAAAAUUUUUGAUGCUCUGUCCUUCAAGAGGUGAAGCCUAAAUUCCUUCCCCUUGAGUGGACUAGACUUAAUUAUGUACUUUCACAAAUAAUGUGGCAUAAAUAACAGUGUGUGACUUCUAGGACUAGGCCAUAAAAAGCAUUGCUGUCUAAAGAGUCUCUCUUGGAUCAUUCUGGGGGAAACCAACUGCCAUGUUGAGAGGACAUACAAGCAAUCCUAUGGAGAGGCCCAUAUUGCGGGGGGAACAGGCCCCCUGCCAAGGGCCAUGCAAGUGAGCCAUUUUGGAAGUAGAUCCUCCAGUUCCAGUCAAGCCUUCAGAUGACUGCAUCCCUGGCCAACCUUUUUACUACAACACCUUAGAGGACAAUGAGUCAGAACCAUCCAGACCCACAGAAUUGUGAGAAAAUAAAUGUUUUUGUUUUAAGCUGCUAAAUUAUGGGGUGAUUUGUUACACAGCAAUAGGUAACUAAUGCCCCCUUUUAUGUUCCCCCCAACCCAGCUACAUUUUUCUCCAUGGUACUUACCACUAUCUGACACACUGUAUAUUUCCCCCACUUAGAAUUGUACCAUUAUAAUAAGGACUUUGUCUUAUUUGCUCCUGUGUCCAACAGUGCCUGGCAAAAAAAAUAGAUAAUAAAUAUGUGUUGGAUGAAUGAAGCAUGGGUCUCUGAAGGUCUAGGUCUGUCUCCGUCUCUGUGAGGUAUAAGACCAGACUGCGGGUAUGAGAGGCAGCCUUUCCUUUUCACAGAUGAAGAGAGAUAAACCAAGUCCCAGUCAAGCAUAUUCCUUCCCCUCAGCCCUUCCCAGUUGUAGCCCUCCUGGCCCAGACCCCAAAAGUGGAUUAACUUUGCUUGAUUGAUUUGGGAGCUGGGGGAGUGACUGCCCAGCCCCUUACCAUUCAACCCAAACCCUACAAAGCGAUCUCCAAACACUCAGAACUGGAAUUUCCCCAAGCCAAUUCCUACCUUUCUAGGAAGACUCUGGCCACCUACCUUUGUCCAUGGACCUCCUCUGAGCAGCCAGGGGAAGCUGUGGUGGGGAAAAGGGAGCAAGCAGGGCACAAGGGUUCUGUGGAUUGCUACCCUCUGCUCUCCAGUCUUCCAGUAGACUUCCAGGGCAUGUCUGUCUGCCUGGCACAUUCACUGAUUCUCCCCUCCCAGCAUCAGGGAGGGUUGGGCAGAGGAGGAGGCUUGGCUCUGCCCCAGGAUACUCACACCAAACAAAGCCAUGGGGGAGGAGGCAUCAGUACCGACAGUGAUUGGAUCACUGGAGCUUCUGGAGGCUGGGGGGUUCUGAUGGGCUCAGAGGUCUGAAAUCUGAGGUGGAGGACACUGGGGCAGCCAAAGGAAUGAAUGGGGUGAGCCUCAGCGUGGCCAGGAAUGGGCCAUAGAGAACCAGGACUUAGUGCUGCAGUAGAAGCUGGGCACAGAAGGGUGCAGAGAAGGGUGGCGGCUGGAGGCAGGGAGAGCAGGGAGGAGGCACCCACCAUGGUCAGACCCACCAUGGUCAGAAGAGCCGGUGGUUUGAGCCAGAGCAAGCUGAGGCUGAGAGGAGUGGACUGAUUGGGAGAGGACAAGGGAGGAGGGAGGAGACAAAGGUCGUGUUUGGAUUCCUGCCUUCUGGGGGUGUGAGGUCAGAAGACAGUCUCUGGUGCCACAGUUUCAUACCUAUGCCAAGUGUCACCCCUACAGACACCUGCUGUUCACUUACACACUUGGCAUCACCUCACAGUGUCCCUCUGUUUGCUUUCCAGCGCCCCCUGCCCCCGAAGCUGGCUGGAAAGAAGGUGGGAGACACCUGUUGGGGAGCUGAGAGCGGCAGAUCCCACAGGGGCCUCUCCCCAUGCGCCCCGCCCGCCCUGCCCCGCUCGGGUCCCGCCCCCGCGGCCGCCGCAAGCAGCGCGGCGAGUGAGCGCACAGCCGCCAGAGGAGCACAGGGCGGCGGGAGCGCACCGCCGGGACCCAGCCGAGGCCAGGGCCGCCUGGGAGGCGGGCGGAGCAAAGGCAGCGCCGUGGAGACGCCAGGGGCAGCGGGCCACGCCAGGCAGGCGGCCCUUUCCUCGGGGUCCCGCCUGGUACCAGGGACCCCCUCAGCUGGGGGACUGCGCCUGGAAGCUGUCAUGGAGGCCCUGCAGAAGCAGCAGGCAGCUCGGCUGGCCCAGGGGGUGGGGCCAUUGGCCCCUGCAUGCCCGCUGCUGCCACCGCAGCCUCCCCUGCCUGACCACCGGACCCUACAGGCCCCUGAGGGGGCCUUGGGGAAUGUUGGGGCUGAGGAAGAGGAAGAUGCUGAAGAAGAUGAGGAGAAGCGGGAGGAAGCCGGGGCAGAGGAGGAGGCAGCUGAGGAGAGCCGUCCAGGGGCCCAGGGCCCCAGCUCGCCUUCUAGCCAGCCCCCUGGACUCCAUCCCCACGAGUGGACCUACGAGGAACAAUUCAAGCAGCUGUAUGAGCUCGAUGCAGACCCCAAGAGGAAGGAAUUUCUGGAUGACCUGUUUAGCUUCAUGCAAAAGAGGGGGACGCCAGUGAACCGCGUGCCCAUCAUGGCGAAGCAGGUGCUCGACCUGUACGCUCUGUUUCGCCUGGUGACCGCCAAGGGCGGCCUGGUGGAAGUCAUCAACCGCAAAGUGUGGCGGGAAGUCACGCGCGGCCUCAGCCUACCCACCACCAUCACCUCGGCCGCCUUCACUCUACGCACCCAGUACAUGAAGUACCUGUACCCGUACGAGUGCGAGACUCGAGCGCUCAGCUCCCCAGGGGAGCUCCAGGCCGCCAUAGACAGCAAUCGGCGCGAGGGCCGUCGCCAGGCUUACACCGCUACUCCGCUCUUCGGCUUGGCAGGGCCGCCCCCUCGGGGCGCUCAGGACCCAGCCUUGGGUCCCGGCCCCGCCCCUCCGGCGACCCAGUCCAGCCCUGGCCCAGCCCAGGGUUCCACCUCCGGCCUGCCAGCGCAUGCAUGCGCUCAGCUGAGUCCAAGCCCUAUUAAGAAAGAGGAGAGUGGAAUUCCAAACCCUUGUCUGGCACUGCCUGUGGGCCUGGCACUGGGACCUACACGGGAGAAAUUGGCACCAGAGGAGCCCCCAGAGAAGAGAGCUGUGCUGAUGGGGCCUAUGGACCCACCUCGACCUUGCAUGCCCCCCAGUUUCCUGCCCCGUGGCAAGGUUCCCCUGAGGGAAGAGCGGCUGGAUGGGCCUCUUAAUCUGGCAGGCAGUGGCAUCAGCAGUAUCAACAUGGCCCUAGAGAUCAACGGGGUGGUCUACACUGGUGUCCUCUUUGCCCGCCGCCAGCCUGUGCCAGCUUCCCAGGGUCCAACCAACCCUGCACCCCCACCCUCCACAGGGCCCCCUUCCAGCAUCUUGCCCUGAGAGGUCCUACUUGAAACUAAGAGUCCCAGCCCCAUUGCUGAGGGGGGAGGAGACCCCCUGCUUUGAUUCUUUCUGGCUGCCCACUCUGGGAC